GAGUCCUUUGGACGGUAAAAUGGCGCCUGUCAGAGUGGGAAACCCAGCUGCAGAGGCUGCAGCCCCGGUCCCCAGCGGCUAAAGGACCCCCGAGCUCGGGGAGGGGGAGGCCGCUCCGGCCCAGCGCUCUGCGCCCUCCGGCUCCCCCUCCCCCUCCUUCCCUGCUCCUUCGCUCUGCAGGUCUCGGAGGACCCCAUCCUAGCCCUACCUGUCUCGGCCCGCAACCUCCCCGAAGCCGUCGGUGCCACUCCCAGCCCAUGUGGGCCCCCGCGGGCUGCCCACGCCUGUCCCCCAGCUCCCCGUUCCGCUGGGCUUUACCCUCGCCAGGGGUGGCUUUCUGAGCCGCCCGCUCCGUGCCCCUCUCUGCAGCCUCUCCUGCCACUCGGGGCCCCCGUUCCCCCUCCCGGCGGCGGGGGGCUGCCCCCGGGGGGCUGGCGGAGCUGGGCCGCGGGGGCCCCGGGGCCGGCGGUGCCGGGGUCAUCGGGAUGAUGCGGACGCAGUGUCUGCUGGGGCUGCGCACGUUCGUGGCCUUCGCCGCCAAGCUCUGGAGCUUCUUCAUUUACCUUCUGCGGAGGCAGAUCCGCACGGUAAUUCAGUACCAAACUGUUCGAUAUGAUAUCCUCCCCUUAUCUCCUGUGUCCCGGAAUCGGCUAGCCCAGGUGAAGAGGAAGAUCCUGGUGCUGGAUCUGGAUGAGACACUUAUUCACUCCCACCAUGAUGGGGUCCUGAGGCCCACAGUCCGGCCUGGUACGCCUCCUGACUUCAUCCUCAAGGUGGUAAUAGACAAACAUCCUGUCCGGUUUUUUGUACAUAAGAGGCCCCAUGUGGAUUUCUUCCUGGAAGUGGUGAGCCAGUGGUACGAGCUGGUGGUGUUUACAGCAAGCAUGGAGAUCUAUGGCUCUGCUGUGGCAGAUAAACUGGACAAUAGCAGAAGCAUUCUUAAGAGGAGAUAUUACAGACAGCACUGCACUUUGGAGUUGGGCAGCUACAUCAAGGACCUCUCUGUGGUCCACAGUGACCUCUCCAGCAUUGUGAUCCUGGAUAACUCCCCAGGGGCUUACAGGAGCCAUCCAG